AGUGCCCUCGCUUCCUGUGCGUCCCCAGGUCACCGCUCGCCCUAGUUCCCAGGCUUUGGCCUCCGGUGGGCGAGAAUCGCGGAGCCUGCGGGGCUGGGCGCCGAAGAGCCGGGCCGGCACCCAAGCGGGCGCGGGGCUGUGCGGGCCAGGCGGAGGCUCAAGCGGGGAUCCCCGAGCACGACCCCCGGAGCCGACGGCGCUGGGGCCCAAGGGGCCGGCCGGGCGGUGACGACGGCGGAGGCGAAGGGGCGGCGGGACCCGGGCCCGGCCCGUGUGCGUCCUCGACGGCCCGGCCCCGGCUCCGCAGGACGGUGAGCCCCAGGGAGACGGAUCUGGGCUCCGGGAGGGACGCCCCGCCUGGAUUUGUCCCGUAGGCCCGGCCCGGGCCCCUCUGGAGCAGAACGGCCUUGGUGAGGUGGACAGGAAGGGACCUCGCGAGCAGACGCGCGCCCGCGACAGCAAUCCCGCCCCGGCCUGUCGGGAGCGGUGGGGCAGAGGCUGCGGAGCCCCAGGAGGAUCUGCCUCCGCUUUCACAGUCCUCCAGAUUUUUCCAAGAGCAGCAGAAAAUGAAUAAAUCCCUGGGGCCAGUGUCAUUCAAGGACGUGGCUGUGGACUUCACCCAGGAGGAAUGGCAGCAGCUGGAUCCUGAGCAGAAGAUAACUUACAGGGAUGUGAUGCUGGAGAACUACAGCAAUCUAGUUUCUGUGGGGUAUCACAUUAUCAAACCGGAUGUUAUCAGCAAGUUGGAGCAAGGAGAAGAGCCAUGGAUAGUAGAAGGAGAAUUCCUACUUCAGAGCUAUCCAGAUGAAGUCUGGCAAACUGAUGACCUAAUAGAGAGAAUCCAGGAAGAGGAAAAUAAACCUUCAAGGCAAACUGUGUUCAUUGAGACCCUGAUUGAAGAGAGAGGUAAUGUUCCUGGUAAAACUUUUGAUGUAGAAACGAACCCUGUUCCUUCAAGAAAAAUAGCCUAUAAAAAUAGCCUCUGUGACUCAUGUGAAAAGUGUUUAACGUCUGUUUCAGAAUAUAUUAGUAGUGAUGGAAGCUAUGCAAGAAUGAAAGCUGAUGAAUGUAGUGGAUGUGGGAAAUCACUCCUCCAUAUUAAGCUUGAGAAAACUCAUCCAGGAGAUCAAGCUUAUGAAUUUAAUCAAAAUGGGGAACCUUAUACUCUAAAUGAAGAAAGUCUUUAUCAGAAAAUUCGUAUUUUGGAGAAACCUUUUGAAUAUAUUGAAUGCCAGAAAGCCUUCCAAAAGGACACUGUUUUUGUUAAUCACAUGGAAGAAAAGCCCUAUAAGUGGAAUGGAUCUGAAAUAGCCUUUCUCCAGAUGUCGGACCUCACUGUACAUCAGACAUCUCAUAUGGAAAUGAAGCCCUAUGAAUGCAGUGAAUGUGGGAAAUCCUUCUGUAAAAAGUCAAAAUUUAUUAUACAUCAGAGGACUCACACAGGAGAGAAACCUUACGAAUGUAAUCAGUGUGGGAAAUCCUUCUGCCAGAAGGGAACCCUUACUGUGCAUCAGAGAACACACACAGGGGAGAAGCCCUAUGAAUGUAAUGAAUGUGGGAAGAACUUUUACCAGAAGUUACACCUCAUUCAGCAUCAGAGAACUCACUCAGGAGAGAAGCCCUAUGAAUGUAGUUAUUGUGGAAAAUCCUUUUGCCAGAAGACACACCUCACACAACAUCAGAGAACACAUUCAGGAGAGAGACCUUAUGUUUGUCAUGACUGUGGGAAAACCUUCUCGCAGAAGUCAGCACUUAAUGACCAUCAGAAAAUUCACACAGGUGUGAAACUCUACAAGUGUAGUGAAUGUGGGAAAUGCUUCUGCCGCAAGUCUACUCUCACGACCCACCUGAGGACCCACACAGGAGAGAAACCGUAUGAAUGUAAUGAGUGUGGAAAAUUCUUCUCUCGGUUGUCAUAUCUCACUGUACAUUAUAGAACUCAUUCAGGAGAGAAACCCUAUGAAUGUAAUGAAUGUGGAAAAACCUUCUACCUGAAUUCAGCCCUCAUGAGACAUCAGAGAGUGCACACAGGAGAGAAACCUUACGAAUGUAAUGAAUGUGGAAAGUUAUUCUCCCAGUUGUCAUACCUCACUAUCCAUCAUAGAACUCAUUCAGGAGUAAAACCCUAUGAAUGUAGUGAAUGUGGGAAAACCUUCUACCAGAACUCAGCCCUUUGUAGACAUCGGAGAAUACACAAAGGAGAGAAGCCCUAUGAAUGCUAUAUAUGUGGAAAAUUCUUCUCUCAGAUGUCAUACCUCACUAUACAUCAUAGAAUUCAUUCAGGAGAGAAGCCCUAUGAAUGUAGUGAAUGUGGGAAAACCUUCUGCCAGAAUUCAGCCCUUAAUCGACAUCAGAGAACACACACAGGAGAGAAAGCCUACGAAUGUUAUGAAUGUGGGAAGUGCUUCUCUCAGAUGUCCUAUCUCACUAUACAUCAUCGAAUUCAUUCAGGAGAGAAACCCUUUGAAUGUAAUGAGUGUGGAAAAGCCUUCUCUCGGAUGUCAUACCUCACUGUACAUUAUAGAACUCAUUCAGGAGAGAAACCCUAUGAGUGUACUGAAUGUGGAAAAAAAUUCUACCACAAAUCAGCAUUCAACAGCCAUCAGAGAAUUCAUAGGAGAGGCAAUAUGAAUGUAAUAGAUGUGGGAAGGCUUCUCUGAAGUCAGACCUCAUUUUAUAUCAGAGAACCCUUUCAGUAUAGUGAAUCAGAAACUCCUGCCUGAAGUCAAACACCUUGUACAUCAGAGAGUUCACACAGGUUAGUGUGGACAUCCCCUUGUGUGUUGGACUCAUAAUCUGAAGACUCACAGAAUGGAAACCAUGAUUAUAACAAGACCACAUGGUAUAACAAUACUAGACUAUAGACAAGUAAAAAUUUAUAAAUAUUAAGAAUGUAUAUACAUGUCACCAUGGAUUGGAACUGUUUUGCAUAUCAGGGAAAUCAUAGCCAAGGGGAAAUCUAUCAGUAUAAGGAAUGUGGAAGACAUAAUCCUUUGGAAACUGUUAAUACUAAAAGAUAUGUUUCUGAUACAAUAGCAAACUUGAAAAAAAAAAAAGAAAUAGAAGAUUCCUGCUGUGAAUAAACAUACUUCUUGUGUAAAUAGAAACUGUAAAGUCAUCAGGAUAGCUAGUUAAGUCGGUAACCUUAAACUCAUGUAAGCAGUUCCCAAAGAACAUAGGACUUAUGUUUGGGGAGAGGGUUGUUUUUAUUACAGUACAUUACAGGAAUUGUAUGUUCACUUCGAAUCAUGUUUGAAAAAACGUUGUAUCCUUAUUUUGUAAUUCAUAUAGUAAGAGUAUUCUAAACAGCACUACAUUAAUAUCAUUUGAUAGGUAUAAAGUAUACUUUUUCUUGCACUCUUCUCUAGGAUUUAAUGCAUUGAUCAUUCUUAAUGAACAAUAUCAGCUCUAAAGGACCAAUGCUUUUAUAAUGUUUUCAACUGUAUCUGAGUCAGCCAGAGAGAUAAAUAUCCAUGUAUAAAAUAGAUAGAAAACUUUGCUUGGUAAUUUAAAAUUAAUAAUGCCAGUUUUCCAAGAGUGAGAAAAUCAUUGCACUCUAUACAGUUUUAAGAUAUACUUAAAAUAUUCCCAUUUGUAUCUAUUUUUUUUUCUACUGUUUUUUAUUUGGACACUUACAUAACAGUGCAGAGCACAAUGCUGUGUAACAUAGGAAUUCACUGUGUUUUCAUUUGAUGUCGUACUGGUUUUAAACCUUGUGCUCUACUCCUUCCUGUUAAUGAAUUAAGAACACAUUCUAACAAGGGUCUGUGGCAGACAUUGCCGAGUGACUUUCUAACAUAGGAAUUCACUGUGUUUUCAUUUGAUGUCGUACUGGUUUUAAACCUUGUGCUCUACUCCUUCCUGUUAAUGAAUUAAGAACACAUUCUAACAAGGGUCUGUGGCAGACAUUGCCGAGUGACUUUCUUAGUCACUCCCUUACUCUGCUGGCGGAGUUUGGUUAUCCAUUUAUCCUCAAAAGGAAGUGAGAUAAAUCCUGAUUAGUUUUAACCAGUGACACUCCCCUUCUCGUUGCCAGCAGUUGAUUUACAGUGGUCACAGGGCCCAAUUCUAGACAUAAAACAAAGGAUAUACCUGACAGACUACUUCUGGAAAAGGUUUUCUCAAAGGCCCAAGGAUUCAAGCAAAGGGAAGUGGAAUCUUGUGGUGAACAGUACCUUGUCUGGAUGUGGUGCCUGGUAACCAUCUUUCAGCAAUGGAUUAUAGUUUAAUCAUGGCCUGAGCAGAAAUACUGAAAGACCCUGAGACCUGGAUGAUGUCUUUGAGCCACCAAACCAAGCAGCCUUGUAGCCACUCCUCCUUUGGACUGUUUCUUUUGUGAGAGACUAAACUUAUUUUUAAGCCAGUUGAUUUAGGAUGCUCUAUUACUAAUAACUGAAGACAUUCUAAUUGGUACAGACUGAAACCUUUAUAGGAGUUAUGCAGUUCAGAAGUGGACUUUAGGUAAGUCAUUUAUUUUAAGCUGUUGAUAUAGAGAUUUAUUUUCUGUAAAUUUUGACGUAAAUAGUUUGAGCAUUAGAAAUCAACUUGAAACAAUAAAAUGUAUGCUUCCUUGAACUGUCAUAUCGUUGACCUGCAAAAUUCACCUUUGGAACGUGACACAAUGUUAGGCAUACCUCCUUUUUUCUAAUACAUGGAAUACAUUUUGUUGGAGGUAAUUUAUGUGAUUCAUAUACCACUGCUACAGUGUUAGCUGACAACAUAUAGUAUGAGGUAAGGAUCUAAUUCUGUUUCCUCUCACAUGAUUACUUGAUAGCUAAGCAUCUGAUUGGUUUACUGCUUUACCACUGAGCUGAAAUGCCGUGUUUUCCAUUUAUUAAAAUCACACAUGGCUCCUGUUUUUGUCACUCAGCACUUUUUCUCCAUAUUCUUCAAGACGAUUGUGAGUAUGGUACGUAACAGGAAUUACAUCUGGUAAGUUGUAUAGUUUUGUGUAGGAACUCUAUAUUCAUAGCAUAUUUGUGGAAAUGAUACCUAUGGAGGUUUCUCACACUGGUGUGUCAUUAUACAUUAAUUGUACAAUAUGCAUUUUCAGUAAAAUAUUUGAAAACUGUAAA